GGAGGAAAUCUACAAGCACCAGGAAGUCAAGAUGCAAGCACCAGCCUUCAGGGACAAGAAACAGGGGGUCUCAGCCAAGAAUCAAGGUGCCCAUGACCCAGACUAUGAGAAUAUCACCUUGGCCUUCAAAAAUCAGGACCAUGCAAAGGGUGGUCAUUCACGACCCACGAGCCAAGUCCCAGCCCAGUGCAGGCCGCCCUCAGACUCCACCCAGGUCCCCUGCUGGUUGUACAGAGCCAUCCUGAGCCUGUACAUCCUCCUGGCCCUGGCCUUUGUCCUCUGCAUCAUCCUGUCAGCCUUCAUCAUGGUGAAGAAUGCUGAGAUGUCCAAGGAGCUGCUGGGCUUUAAAAGGGAGCUUUGGAAUGUCUCAAACUCCGUACAAGCAUGCGAAGAGAGACAGAAGAGAGGCUGGGAUUCCGUUCAGCAGAGCAUCACCAUGGUCAGGAGCAAGAUUGAUAGAUUAGAGACGACAUUAGCAGGCAUAAAAAACAUUGACACAAAGGUACAGAAAAUCUUGGAGGUGCUGCAGAAAAUGCCACAGUCCUCACCUCAAUAAAUGAGAGGACAUUGUGGCAGCCAAAGCCACAACUUGGAAGAUGGGGCUGCACCUGCCAACGAAGACGGGAAAUGACCCCCCCCCCCCAGCCUAGUGUGAACCUGCCCCUCGUCCCACGUAUAGAAAAACCUCGAGUCAUGGUGAAUGAGUGUCUCGGAGUUGCUCGUGUGUGUGUACACCUGCGUGCGUGUGUGUGCGUGUGUGCGCGUGUGUUCGUGUAUGUGCGUGUGUGCGUGCGCGUGUGUGUGCAUUUUGCAAAGGGUGGACAUUUCAGUGUAUCUCCCAGAAAGGUGAUGAAUGAAUAGGACUGAGAGUCACAGUGAAUGUGGCAUGCAUGCCUGUGUCAUGUGACAUAUGUGAGUCUCGGCAUGUCACGGUGGGUGGCUGUGUCUGAGCACCUCCAGCAGAUGUCACUCUGAGUGUGGGUGUUGGUGACAUGCAUUGCACGGGCCUGUCUCCCUGUUUGUGUAAACAUACUAGAGUAUACUGCGGCGUGUUUUCUGUCUACCCAUGUCAUGGUGGGGGAGAUUUAUCUCCGUACAUGUGGGUGUCGCCAUGUGUGCCCUGUCACUAUCUGUGGCUGGGUGAACGGCUGUGUCAUUAUGAGUGUGCCGAGUUAUGCCACCCUGUGUGCUCAGGGCACAUGCACACAGACAUUUAUCUCUGCACUCACAUUUUGUGACUUAUGAAGAUAAAUAAAGUCAAGGGAAAACAG